AGAAACAUCCUGCAGCAUCUCCGUCUCCGGAGGAAAAAUACAUUUGUCUGGGCGAACUCCGGUGGAAAAGCGCCCCAGGCUGCCACAGCCUAGAGAUCUUGGGGCUGCAGCCCUCGCGGCCUGCCGAGGGAGCAGGGGGCGCCCGUGGAACUGGCUCCCUGCAGCUCUGCGGCUACACGCGGACCUCGGCUGUGUGCGAGGUGGCGGAGGAGGCUGGCCGGGUGCGAAUCCGUACCCAGCCCCAGCAUCUUCCACCUGCUGAGGACCACCGCUCAGCCAUGGGCUACCAGAGGCAGGAGCCUGUCAUCCCGCCGCAGAGAGAUUUAGAUGACAGAGAAACCCUUGUUUCUGAACAUGAGUAUAAAGAGAAAACCUGUCAGUCUGCUGCUCUUUUUAAUGUUGUCAACUCGAUUAUAGGAUCUGGUAUAAUAGUAGCCCCAUUUUGACUCCAGAGUCUGUCUUUCUUAAUAUUCCAUAACCCUUCUGUGCUCCUUAUUAUCCUCUCUGCUUUCUUGGCUAGCAGGAUUGCCUUAUUCAAUGAAGCAAGCUGGGUUUCCUUUGGGAAUAUUGCUUUUAUUCUGGGUUUCAUAUGUUACAGACUUUUCCCUUGUUUUAUUGAUAAAAGGAGGGGCCCUCUCUGGAACAGAUACCUACCAGUCUUUGGUCAAUAAAACUUUCGGCUUUCCAGGGUAUCUGCUCCUCUCUGUUCUUCAGUUUUUGUAUCCUUUUAUAGCAAUGAUAAGUUACAAUAUAAUAGCUGGAGAUACUUUGAGCAAAGUUUUUCAAAGAAUCCCAGGAGUUGAUCCUGAAAACGUGUUUAUUGGUCGCCACUUCAUUAUUGGACUUUCCACAGUUACCUUUACUCUGCCUUUAUCCUUGUACCGAAAUAUAGCAAAGCUUGGAAAGGUCUCCCUCAUCUCUACAGGUUUAACAACUCUGAUUCUUGGAAUUGUAAUGGCAAGGGCAAUUUCACUGGGUCCACACAUACCAAAAACAGAAGACGCUUGGGUAUUUGCAAAGCCCAAUGCCAUUCAAGCGGUCGGGGUUAUGUCUUUUGCAUUUAUUUGCCACCAUAACUCCUUCUUAGUUUACAGUUCUCUAGAAGAACCCACAGUAGCUAAGUGGUCCCGCCUUAUCCAUAUGUCCAUCGUGAUUUCUGUAUUUAUCUGUAUAUUCUUUGCUACAUGUGGAUACUUGACAUUUACUGGCUUCACCCAAGGGGACUUAUUUGAAAAUUACUGCAGAAAUGAUGACCUGGUAACAUUUGGAAGAUUUUGUUAUGGUGUCACUGUCAUUUUGACAUACCCUAUGGAAUGCUUUGUGACAAGAGAGGUAAUUGCCAAUGUGUUUUUUGGUGGGAAUCUUUCAUCGGUUUUCCACAUUGUUGUAACAGUGAUGGUCAUCACUGUAGCCACGCUUGUGUCAUUGCUGAUUGAUUGCCUCGGGAUAGUUCUAGAACUCAAUGGUGUGCUCUGUGCAACUCCCCUCAUUUUUAUCAUUCCAUCAGCCUGUUAUCUGAAACUGUCUGAAGAACCAAGGACACACUCCGAUAAGAUUAUGUCUUGUGUCAUGCUUCCCAUUGGUGCUGUGGUGAUGGUUUUUGGAUUCGUCAUGGCUAUUACAAAUACUCAAGACUGCACCCAUGGGCAGGAAAUGUUCUACUGCUUUCCUGACAAUUUCUCUCUCACAAAUACCUCAGAGUCUCAUGUUCAGCAGACAACACAACUUUCUACUUUAAAUAUUAGUAUCUUUCAAUGAGUUGACUGCUUUAAAAAUAUGUAUGUUUUCAUAGACUUUAAAACACAUAACAUUUACGCUUGCUUUAGUCUGUAUUUAUGUUAUAUAAAAUUAUUAUUUUGGCUUUUAUCAAGACUUGGCUUUUAUGAGUAGUGCAAUAUAAAAGAUAAAGAAAAGAAAAAUUGAAUGUAUUUCACCUUUAACUGGAACAAAAUAAGGGUUUUGUUCUAAUGACUGCACUACACUAAUGCUAAUUGAAGAAGGGAGAGUUAAGCCUUUAGCAUUUUCUGCCAUCCCCCUUUUAUUUAAUAUGCAAACCAGUAUAUUGUGCUCCAAAAUAAGUAGGUGAUUGUGGGUUGGAAUUUUGUGUAGAUGUCUUUUGGUGGGGGGGUGUGGGGGGUGGGCAUUUUCUUUGUCCUUAAAAGUCUGUGGAACUGAAGAGAAGGGAAACCCAAAACGAUUGAAAAGAAGACAUAUCCCAAGAACAAAGAGGAGCUCUCCGUUAUAAUUUCAGCAGCAUCCUUUGUUUAAAGGGAAAUGGAUCCCUGGAGAAAUGAGCAAAGACCUCUCCAUGUGAGGAAUCCUGAAUCAUAGACUGGCUGUGAGGAGCAAGGUGUGUAAAGAAUCAAAAUCACCUCCCAUCUUCUGAUGCUGUGGGAAUACAAUGGUAGCACCAUUCUAAAACAGAAAAACAAACAAACAAACAAAAAAAACAAAAACAAAAAACAGUUGUUCUGUGGCAAGAACCUAAGAGAUUGGUGAUAUGGACCUGUUGGAUUUUUAGUGCUGUCAGGAAUGUACAACUGGAAGCUGAACUUUGAAACUAGAAACGUGUAAGAAGAAUCAGGGCUACAGAAGAAGCUUUCUCAGUCCACUGGGGGUUCCUCAGAGAGAUUUCUGGGAGCUCUUGUUGACUGGGUCUUUGGGAGCAGAUAGUGAGAUGGAGUUUAUCAUAACUAAUGGGAGAGAGGGGAAAGCAGGAUUGUUAGGGAGAGGUAGAACUGCAGUGCAGGCUGACCUCAGCCAAAUCCACAGGGAAGCUGGUGCAUACAUGACCCAUCAGAGUUGUCCCUGUUCAAGGGUAAUAGCCCAGUUUUGAUACUGCUGCCUCCAUCAGUCAUUUAAUGUGAGCAUCUGGAGAAGGAUGAGUUCUUGGGCUAGGCAGCUCUUUGCAGCAGAGCAAACCCUAAAGGAACUGAGAGCUCGAGGUGGUCUACUGAUAGCUUUGUCACCACAUGCUUCCUUACAGGGGUAUCUGGGAGACACAGCUGUGCCCACCACAGAUGCCCUCGGUUUACUGAGGAUUUUUAAAUGAUUUUUUAAUGAGGACUUUGUGUCUUUGUAUGUAUGACAAUCUUCAAAAAGUAACAUGAAAAUCUGGGGCCAUCUGGAUGGCUUCCUUAUAUCAAGUAUCACCUAAGAUUUUCAUUUCAUUUGUAUUCCAAUCAGGUUGUCCAUCUGUGGCACUAUAUUAAUUGUUGCCAAAUAACGAGAAACUAUCACAAGCAGAGUUAAUACAUAUAUGAUGAGUUUGUACAAAUCAAAUGCAAAAAGAAAUCCUACAGGAAGUGUAUAAAGGGUAGGUUCACAGUAGUUUGAAUAAAGUGGCAAGAGCUGAGUCACUGUGUGACUCAUAGUGAGAAAGGCCUAUUGAACAUAAAGGAAGAUGCAUUUUAGCAGGUAGAACCAUGCUCAGGGUUUUAGUGGUGAUUUAUUUUUUCAAUAAAAUAUUAUCCUUACCAUUAAAUUAAUUUAAAUUCUGUUGGGUAACUUUUCUGUAUUUAACUUAUAAAUUUGUUUUUUUAUAGUUAAGGGUCAUAGGCUAAGCAGUUUGUGCCUGUUUUUAGAUUGGUACAUGUUUAGGUAAAAUAUAAUAAAAAUGCUUUCAUUCCAUGUAAGAAAUGAGGAAAUGUAAGAAAUUUUUGCCACAGUCUGUCAUUACAUUGCUCAAGACUGAGAAACACUGACCUACAUAAUUAUUAAAUAAAGUCAUGAGGGAUGAGAUCUCUAAGCAUGUACAAAGAAAAGUAUGUCAAGGAUAACAUAAUUUAGCACGUAACCAUCUCUUAUCUUGUACUUUGGUGUUGCUUCAUACUCUUCAAGUAGAUGAAAGCUCCUGGUAGGAACUGAGCGCAGCAUUAGUGCCUAAUAAACAUGUAUUGGUUUAUUUAUUUUUAAUCAGCUGUAGAACAAGACUGCUUAUGACCCAGUUAUUAGCUGCACGGAUUACCGACAUCUUUCAAAUUAUAAUUUAAUAAAUCUUAGGAACUCACAUUUAUUUUGCAAGAAUACUUGUAUGCUUAUUUUGCCACCAUGCAUAACUGCAAGAACCCCACCCCUCAAUCUAUUUUCUGCCUCAGUUCAAUAAGAGAUUCCCCUGAAAAUCUUUCCAUCCCUGCCACUUGUUGCCCCUAACAAAGCAACUUGAAGGUUUUAAACCAGUUUUUGAAGCUGUCAAUACACUUAAAUGUAUAAAGCACUUCUUAACUUUAAAAAGGUGGUGGUAGGCAAGAAUCACAUCUUUACACACAAAUGAGAACAUCUAGCAAUACACUUCCUUUAAGGAUAUAAGUUGGAUAGCAUCUGUGUAAUUUAGAAAUUGAGUCAUUGUUCACUUAUUAUAGAAUCUUUAUUAUCAAAACUAACUUGAACCAUCUUCAAACAUCAGAAUGGGUAAACUGUCUAUGACCAUACCUUCCUGAACGCACCAGAUCUCAUCUGAUCUUGGAAGCUAAGUAUGGUCUGGCCUUGUUAGUACUUGGAUGGGAGAAGAAGUAAACUGCCUUGCCUGGACUAUUUCCAAUGAUGCCAAACAAUAAUUGUUGCCCCUUGUCUUUCUUAAAAGGAGACUGCAUCCAUUUAACCAAACUAAGAAAUUUUCAAUUAGUCCUCUGCUGAAGUCAUACUAUACACAUCUACUUAAUUAAAGAUACAUUUAUUGAAGAGAACAGGUCUCCUCCUGGUUUAUCUGCUAUAGCCUUGCUUAGGAAAGGAAUAAUAGUCUGUCUUUUAAUUAGGUGUGGCUAUUGAUUGGAGCAAAUGUUGUCAGGUGGCCCAAGCAUGAAUCAAUGAGUGACCAUGAGGUCACCCAUCAGUGAGGGUACCCAUGAAUGCUUUACUAACUGUGGCAAGGAUAAUAAUUUGCUACCUCAAUAGAAUAAGCGCUUUUAAGAAUGUAUGCUUAUUCUAAAAAAUGUGUAAAGAAUUUGCCAAGAUAGCAGAGCAAAUAUGUAGAGUGGACCAGAGAUGCUGUGACCUAGAGAACACAUAGACCAGGAGAGAAAGAAAAGAGCCCAGUCUUUGUCUAGGGUAGUGGCUUUUAAACUUGGACAUGUGUCAGAAUCACCUGGAGGCCUUGUUGAAACACAGAUUGCUGGGCUUCACCCCCACAGUUUCUGAUUCAGUACUUGGAGUGGGGCCUCAGAAUUUCUAUUUCUGAAAAGUUCCCAGGUGAUGCUGCUGCUGCUGGUUCAGGGACCACGUUUGAAAAAGGCUGGAAGUUGGACAUAAGAAAGUGCCAGAUGGAGCCAUCUGUUUAGAGGCUGGGACACAAUACAAGCAAGAUGUAGGAAUACCAUGCUAGAUCUCAGGGAAGAAAAUGAGGCUGGAGAUGUAGGAGGGAGAGCAAUUGGUACAUAUUAAAUGUGUUAUCCUUUGCCUCUUUGAAAAAUCAUCUAGAGACACAGUGAGAAGAGGAGAAACCACGACAAUAAUAUUAGUGAAGAGCAAUGACAAAGGACAUGGGAGGAGAAUUAACAAGGGAGAAAAUAGAGAUUACAACCCCAAAUCAACACAGUUAUGCUGGUUAAGCUGCAGGCCUGGUUCUGAGCCUGCCAGCACUCAGGGAAGGUUACCUGAGUUUCAUGGCUGCCAUUGUGAGAAUGAAGAAAAUAUAUCAGUUUCUCAAAAGAACACCAAGUUUUCCAAGGACUAAACUCUCAGCAGAAUGGCUUACUUGGAAAAUUACAUAGGGAACAUGAGUAAAACUGGGUUAUGAAUGAUAAUGUCAUUCAGAUAAAGAAUUUACAUGGUUGUCUUUUGUUAAGACACUUUUUCAUUCCAUUAAUGUUUGCUCAUUGAUAAUAAAGAUUAUCAAUACAUUUA